GUCAUUCUGCAAAAGCUGCCCGAACAGGCUUUCCUCUGAAAAGCAGUGCCGUUCCUUUUUAGAAAGACUGAAUCUAAAUGUUGUCUCUGGAGACAAGAAGCCUUCAGUAUGUUAAAUUACUUUCAUUAUGUAUUUUCAGAUGCUUAUUGAUUCCACAGUAGGAAGAGUGAGAGACUGCAGCAGCCUCUAAGCAGCACUACAUGUUCCAUACAUUAGCAGUACUGCUGAAACAAUGGCACACUACAGACACAUAUUUUCAUUAAGGUCAUUUUCGAAGAGAUGUUUAUGACCCUCUUCCCCCAGUCCUCUACUAACAAGUGAACAAAAUGAAUCAAUCCAAACUGGAAAUGCUUCAACUACAUCAAGAAUUUAUCAAAUCUUUAGCAGAGGGCCAAUAGCAGCUAAUUCAGUAUUUACAACUGACAAUAUGAAGAAUGCAAUUGACUGAGCAUCUCCCUAGCUGUCUGAACUACGAACUGCAAGAUGUUCUUGUAACACGACUUUAAGACAUUAAGGAGUUAAAACCAGGGAAUAGGUCUACAUUACUGAUGGAAUAUAAAAAAUCAACUGUAUCCUAAGAAGAUGCUACAUAAAAUAACCACAAAAAGAAAAACAAUAUAACUGUAAAAGCCUGAAAAGAAUUUUUAAAAGGGGAAGUUUAUACUUUCAUAUACCAGAAUUGUGGAAGUUACUGAUUCUGGAAGACAUAAUGAAACAUGAAUUUCCAAAAAGAAAAGAAAAUACUUUAUCAGCACACAAAAGGAAGAUUUAGGAAGUGUUUUCUGCACUAAAUAUUCAGAUAUUCAUAUCAAUUGGUAUGACUAAUGGAUUUUUCUAUCUGACUUUUAUGACCAAUUAUGUAUCCUCUUCUAAUGAAAACAAACAAAAUUAAACAGCAGAUGGUUUUUAUCAAAAGGACAUGGCCUGGAUUUAUAAUAUAAAGCAAGUUAUGUGAUCAAGAAAUCAUUUCAAAAUAGUGAGCACUGCUAUUAAAAACAGAUUUACAAUGGUAACAAAAGGAUGUCUAAAUAUAUUUUAGAAGCUACAAACGUUAUGUUUCCUUUUUUGUUUUCACAUAUUCUGGAAAAUAAAGAAAUAUUAUCAUGUACUCCAUCAAAGGGAAACAUAAUUCCUAUCAUCUGAGGAAAUUCCUCUUGGCCGUGACUUUUUAAAGCAAAACAAAUACAAAUAUUAUGUACUGUUCUUUAGAAAUCCAUCAGCCAACUAAAUCUCAUAAUGCAUGCAGUUGAAGUAUUGGAGAGAAAACGAAAGAAUUCCUACAAGACAUGAAAUAAAACACAGCUACUUCACUGUUGUCAGGUAAAAAUUCAUGUCAAAAUCUGUCAAUGAUAUCAUGUAUCAAUUUGCCAAAAACUGUCAUAGUGAACCAAAAGGCCCAUAAGGCAACAGCAAACAGGGAAAAAAACCAACUGCUCCAAAAGAAUGUGUUUUUCUCCCAUUCUGGAAAUCAACAUGCAGUCUGAAUCUAACAUUACAGUGCGAGAUGACAUUGAUGACAUCAACACCAAUAUGUACCAACCACUAUCAUAUCCGUUAAGCUUUCAAGUGUCUCUCACCGGAUUUCUUAUGUUAGAAAUUGUGUUGGGACUUGGCAGCAACCUCACUGUAUUGGUACUUUACUGCAUGAAAUCCAACUUAAUCAACUCUGUCAGUAACAUUAUUACAAUGAAUCUUCAUGUACUUGAUGUAAUAAUUUGUGUGGGAUGUAUUCCUCUAACUAUAGUUAUCCUUCUGCUUUCACUGGAGAGUAACACUGCUCUCAUUUGCUGUUUCCAUGAGGCUUGUGUAUCUUUUGCAAGUGUCUCAACAGCAAUCAACGUUUUUGCUAUCACUUUGGACAGAUAUGACAUCUCUGUAAAACCUGCAAACCGAAUUCUGACAAUGGGCAGAGCUGUAAUGUUAAUGAUAUCCAUUUGGAUUUUUUCUUUUUUCUCUUUCCUGAUUCCUUUUAUUGAGGUAAAUUUUUUCAGUCUUCAAAGUGGAAAUACCUGGGAAAACAAGACACUUUUAUGUGUCAGUACAAAUGAAUACUACACUGAACUGGGAAUGUAUUAUCACCUGUUAGUACAGAUCCCAAUAUUCUUUUUCACUGUUGUAGUAAUGUUAAUCACAUACACCAAAAUACUUCAGGCUCUUAAUAUUCGAAUAGGCACAAGAUUUUCAACAGGGCAGAAGAAGAAAGCAAGAAAGAAAAAGACAAUUUCUCUAACCACACAACAUGAGGCUACAGACAUGUCACAAAGCAGUGGUGGGAGAAAUGUAGUCUUUGGUGUAAGAACUUCAGUUUCUGUAAUAAUUGCCCUCCGGCGAGCUGUGAAACGACACCGUGAACGACGAGAAAGACAAAAGAGAGUCUUCAGGAUGUCUUUAUUGAUUAUUUCUACAUUUCUUCUCUGCUGGACACCAAUUUCUGUUUUAAAUACCACCAUUUUAUGUUUAGGCCCAAGUGACCUUUUAGUAAAAUUAAGAUUGUGUUUUUUAGUCAUGGCUUAUGGAACAACUAUAUUUCACCCUCUAUUAUAUGCAUUCACUAGACAAAAAUUUCAAAAGGUCUUGAAAAGUAAAAUGAAAAAGCGAGUUGUUUCUAUAGUAGAAGCUGAUCCCCUGCCUAAUAAUGCUGUAAUACACAACUCUUGGAUAGAUCCUAAAAGAAACAAAAAAAUUACCUUUGAAGAUAGUGAAAUAAGAGAAAAAUGUUUAGUGCCUCAGGUUGUCACAGACUAGAGAAAAGUCUCAGUUUCACCAAAUCCACAUUCAAAUGAGUUUUAAAUUUAAAUUGUAAAAACUGAUAUUACUGCCAAAUAUAAGAAAAAUAUUUUAAGUAUUGGUUAUGUUGUAAAUUUUCAAUGUGAAUGUCAAUUAGAUAGGUCAUAUAUAUUCAAUUUCUUCAUUACUUAAUGUAUUUGUUGCAUGGCAGUUUGUUAAAGUACUAUCAUGUGUAUAUUUUGUCAAUAUUAUGUCCAACAGAAAAUAUUCAUGUAAGUCAUAUUUUUUAAGGAAUAAAUACAUAGCCUUAAAACAGUGUAUAACUUUAAAAUGUAACUGA